CCCUGGGGAAGAGAAGCUGAGAGGAACUCCUCACUCAGCUAGCUUCAGGAGCCAUGACAUCAUCUCUACCAUGGAAAUUCCACUCACUCUCCUGUGCCCCCACAUUUGUCCUAGGCCUCAGAGUCCCUAUAAAGAGAGAUUCCCAACUCAGUAUCAGCACAGGACACAGCUAGGUUCUGAAGCUUCUGAGUUCUGCAGCCUCACCUCUGAGAAAACCUCUUUGCCACCAAUACCAUGAAGCUCUGCGUGACUGUCCUGUCUCUCCUCGUGCUAGUAGCUGCCUUCUGCUCUCUAGCACUCUCAGCACCAAUGGGCUCAGACCCUCCCACCGCCUGCUGCUUUUCUUACACCGCGAGGAAGCUUCCUCGCAACUUUGUGGUAGAUUACUAUGAGACCAGCAGCCUCUGCUCCCAGCCAGCUGUGGUAUUCCAAACCAAAAGAGGCAAGCAAGUCUGCGCUGACCCCAGUGAGUCCUGGGUCCAGGAGUACGUGUAUGACCUGGAACUGAACUGAGCUGCUCAGAGACAGGAAGUCUUCAGGGAAGGUCACCUGAGCCUGGAUGCUUCUCCAUGAGCCGCAUCUCCUCCAUACUCAGGACUCCUCUCCGCAGUUCCUGUCUCUUCUCUUAAUGUAAUCUCUUUUAUGUGCUGUAUUAUUGUAUUAGGUGUUAUUUCCAUUAUUUAUAUUAGUUUAGCCAAAGGAUAAGUGUCCCCUAUGGGGAUGGUCCACUCUCACUCUUUCUCUGCUGUUGCAAAUACAUGGAUAACACCGUUAAUUCCAUGUGUUUUCAUAAUAAAACUUUAAAAUAAAAUGCAAACAGUU